GGCAACUUCUCCUCCUGCAGCCGGGAGCGGCCUGCCUGCCUCCCUGCGCACCCGCAGCCUCCCCCGCUGCCUCCCUAGGGCUCCCCUCCGGCCGCCAGCGCCCAUUUUUCAUUCCCUAGAUAGAGAUACUUUGCGCGCACACACAUACAUACGCGCGCAAAAAGGAAAAAAAAAAAAAAAAGCCCACCCUCCAGCCUCGCUGCAAAGAGAAAACCGGAGCAGCCGCAGCUCGCAGCUCGCAGCUCGCAGCCCGCAGCCCGCAGAGGACGCCCAGAGCGGCGAGCGGGCGGGCAGACGGACCGACGGACUCGCGCCGCGUCCACCUGUCGGCCGGGCCCAGCCGAGCGCGCAGCGGGCACGCCGCGCGCGCGGAGCAGCCGUGCCCGCCGCCCGGGCCCCGCGCCAGGGCGCACACGCUCCCGCCCCCCUACCCGGCCCGGGCGGGAGUUUGCACCUCUCCCUGCCCGGGUGCUCGAGCUGCCGUUGCAAAGCCAACUUUGGAAAAAGUUUUUUGGGGGAGACUUGGGCCUUGAGGUGCCCAGCUCCGCGCUUUCCGAUUUUGGGGGCCUUUCCAGAAAAUGUUGCAAAAAAGCUAAGCCGGCGGGCAGAGGAAAACGCCUGUAGCCGGCGAGUGAAGACGAACCAUCGACUGCCGUGUUCCUUUUCCUCUUGGAGGUUGGAGUCCCCUGGGCGCCCCCACACGGCUAGACGCCUCGGCUGGUUCGCGACGCAGCCCCCCGGCCGUGGAUGCUCACUCGGGCUCGGGAUCCGCCCAGGUAGCGGCCUCGGACCCAGGUCCUGCGCCCAGGUCCUCCCCUGCCCCCCAGCGACGGAGCCGGGGCCGGGGGCGGCGGCGCCCGGGGGCCAUGCGGGUGAGCCGCGGCUGCAGAGGCCUGAGCGCCUGAUCGCCGCGGACCCGAGCCGAGCCCACCCCCCUCCCCAGCCCCCCACCCUGGCCGCGGGGGCGGCGCGCUCGAUCUACGCGUCCGGGGCCCCGCGGGGCCGGGCCCGGAGUCGGCAUGAAUCGCUGCUGGGCGCUCUUCCUGUCUCUCUGCUGCUACCUGCGUCUGGUCAGCGCCGAGGGGGACCCCAUUCCCGAGGAGCUUUAUGAGAUGCUGAGUGACCACUCGAUCCGCUCCUUUGAUGAUCUCCAACGCCUGCUGCACGGAGACCCCGGAGAGGAAGAUGGGGCCGAGUUGGACCUGAACAUGACCCGCUCCCACUCUGGAGGCGAGCUGGAGAGCUUGGCUCGUGGAAGAAGGAGCCUGGGUUCCCUGACCAUUGCUGAGCCGGCCAUGAUCGCCGAGUGCAAGACGCGCACCGAGGUGUUCGAGAUCUCCCGGCGCCUCAUAGACCGCACCAACGCCAACUUCCUGGUGUGGCCGCCCUGUGUGGAGGUGCAGCGCUGCUCCGGCUGCUGCAACAACCGCAACGUGCAGUGCCGCCCCACCCAGGUGCAGCUGCGACCUGUCCAGGUGAGAAAGAUCGAGAUUGUGCGGAAGAAGCCAAUCUUUAAGAAGGCCACGGUGACGCUGGAAGACCACCUGGCAUGCAAGUGUGAGACAGUGGCAGCUGCACGGCCUGUGACCCGAAGCCCGGGGGGUUCCCAGGAGCAGCGAGCCAAAACGCCCCAAACUCGGGUGACCAUUCGGACGGUGCGAGUCCGCCGGCCCCCCAAGGGCAAGCACCGGAAAUUCAAGCACACGCAUGACAAGACGGCACUGAAGGAGACCCUUGGAGCCUAGGGGCAUCGGCAGGAGAGUGUGUGGGCAGGGUUAUUUAAUAUGGUAUUUGCUGUAUUGCCCCCAUGGGGUCCUUGGAGUGAUAAUAUUGUUUCCCUCGUCCGUCUGUCUCGAUGCCUGAUUCGGACGGCCAAUGGUGCUUCCCCCACCCCUCCACGUGUCCGUCCACCCUUCCAUCAGCGGGUCUCCUCCCAGCGGCCUCCGGCGUCUUGCCCAGCAGCUCAAGAAGAAAAAGAAGGACUGAACUCCAUCGCCAUCUUCUUCCCUUAACUCCAAGAACUUGGGAUAAGAGUGUGAGAGAGACUGAUGGGGUCGCUCUUUGGGGGAAACGGGCUCCUUCCCCUGCACCUGGCCUGGGCCACACCUGAGCGCUGUGGACUGUCCUGAGGAGCCCUGAGGACCUCUCAGCAUAGCCUGCCUGAUCCCUGAACCCCUGGCCAGCUCUGAGGGGAGGCACCUCCAGGCAGGCCAGGCUGCCUCGGACUCCAUGGCUAAGACCACAGACGGGCACACAGACUGGAGAAAACCCCUCCCACGGUGCCCAAACACCAGUCACCUCGUCUCCCUGGUGCCUCUGUGCACAGUGGCUUCUUUUCGUUUUCGUUUUGAAGACGUGGACUCCUCUUGGUGGGUGUGGCCAGCACACCAAGUGGCUGGGUGCCCUCUCAGGUGGGUUAGAGAUGGAGUUUGCUGUUGAGGUGGCUGUAGAUGGUGACCUGGGUAUCCCCUGCCUCCUGCCACCCCUUCCUCCCCACACUCCACUCUGAUUCACCUCUUCCUCUGGUUCCUUUCAUCUCUCUACCUCCACCCUGCAUUUUCCUCUUGUCCUGGCCCUUCAGUCUGCUCCACCAAGGGGCUCUUGAACCCCUUAUUAAGGCCCCAGAUGAUCCCAGUCACUCCUCUCUAGGGCAGAAGACUAGAGGCCAGGGCAGCAAGGGACCUGCUCAUCAUAUUCCAACCCAGCCACGACUGCCAUGUAAGGUUGUGCAGGGUGUGUACUGCACAAGGACAUUGUAUGCAGGGAGCACUGUUCACAUCAUAGAUAAAGCUGAUUUGUAUAUUUAUUAUGACAAUUUCUGGCAGAUGUAGGUAAAGAGGAAAAGGAUCCUUUUCCUAAUUCACACAAAGACUCCUUGUGGACUGGCUGUGCCCCUGAUGCAGCCUGUGGCUUGGAGUGGCCAAAUAGGAGGGAGACUGUGGUAGGGGCAGGGAGGCAACACUGCUGUCCACAUGACCUCCAUUUCCCAAAGUCCUCUGCUCCAGCAACUGCCCUUCCAGGUGGGUGUGGGACACCUGGGAGAAGGUCUCCAAGGGAGGGUGCAGCCCUCUUGCCCGCACCCCUCCCUGCUUGCACACUUCCCCAUCUUUGAUCCUUCUGAGCUCCACCUCUGGUGGCUCCUCCUAGGAAACCAGCUCGUGGGCUGGGAAUGGGGGAGAGAAGGGAAAAGAUCCCCAAGACCCCCUGGGGUGGGAUCUGAGCUCCCACCUCCCUUCCCACCUACUGCACUUUCCCCCUUCCCGCCUUCCAAAACCUGCUUCCUUCAGUUUGUAAAGUCGGUGAUUAUAUUUUUGGGGGCUUUCCUUUUAUUUUUUAAAUGUAAAAUUUAUUUAUAUUCCGUAUUUAAAGUUGUAAAAAAAAAUAACCACAAAACAAAACCAAAUGAAUCCGCCGGAGGUCUGUCUGUUGGCAUCGUGCGUGACAAUUAACCUUUCUGCCUUGGCAGGAUGUGCCGACAGCUUGCGGCGUGUUCCUCUCACUCUGGGAGCCUCAGGCGUGAUCUCACACACUGGCGUGCACAUACACACACACACACAUACAUGCUCACACAUGCGUGCACAUACACGCAGGCCUGCAACUUGGGGGAGGCCUCUGUCUGGCGGGAAGAAGAGACACACAGGCUACUCUGUUGGUCUUGGUCCUGGCACAGCUCCUGACACGUGGACUUGUGCGUGUCUCUGGCAGUGACGAGAGAUGGGUUUCUGCAG